AGUGUUGUUUCCGGAGGCGCCUAAGUGAUCCCGCAGCGACUCUGAGGAGGACCCUGAGGGUCGGGCAUUCUUGCCCUGACCGGCCUCUGCUGGACGCCCACCGGGGAAUCAGGGAGAUACACGGGGCCCCGGCUUCCAGGAGCGCAGCCAGGCCACAGCCCUGAGGACGGGCAAACCCACCCAGGCGCGGUGAGAGGGAGGCCGCCCAGGCCUGGGGCCUGGCGGCAGGGGAUGAAGUGGACCAGAGCCCCGCAAAUCCUAACGUGGGUGAGCAGUGAGCCUGUGUGGCUGCGAGUGGCUCCGUUUUGGGGCUGUUUGUUCCUGCAGCAAAUGAUGCCAGCCCUGACGGAACCAGUGCACGUCCACCACGAGCUGCCCACGUCCUCUCCAGGAAGGGACCCGGGUCCACGAGCUGCCCACGUCCUCUCCAGGAAGGGACCCGGGUCCACGAGCUGCCCACGUCCUCUCCAGGAGGGGACACCGGGUUCACGAGCUGCCCACGCCCUCUCCAGGAGGGGACACCGGGUUCACGAGCUGCCCACGUCCUCUCCAGGAGGGGACACCGGGUUCAUGAGCUGCCCACGCCCUUUCCAGGAAGGGACCCCGGGUUCACGAGCUGCCCACGUCCUCUCCAGGAGGGGACACCGGGGACCCCGGGUUCACGAGCUGCCCACGUCCUCUCCAGGAAGGGACCCCGGGUCCACGAGCUGCCCACGUCCUCUCCAGGAAGGGACCCGGGUCACGAACUGCCCACGUCCUCUCCAGGAAGGGACCCCGGGUUCACGAGCUGCCCACGUCCUCUCCAGGAGGGGACACCGGGUUCACGAGCUGCCCACGCCCUCUCCAGGAAGGGACCCCGGGUUCAUGAGCUGCCCACGUCCUCUCCAGGAAGGGACCCGGGUCACGAACUGCCCACGCCCUCUCCAGGAGGGGACCCGGGUCACGAGCUGCCCACGUCGUCUCCAGGAAGGGACCCGGGUCACGAGCUGCCCACGUCCUCUCCAGGAAGGGACCCGGGUCACGAACUGCCCACGCGCUCUCCAGGAGGGGACACCGGGUUCACGAGCUGCCCACGCCCUCUCCAGGAAGGGACCCCGGGUUCACGAGCUGCCCACGUCCUCUCCAGGAGGGGACACCGGGUUCACGAGCUGCCCACGUCCUCUCCAGGAGGGGACACCGGGUUCACGAGCUGCCCACGCCCUCUCCAGGAGGGGACACCGGGUUCACGAGCUGCCCACGUCCUCUCCAGGAAGGGACCCGGGUCACGAGCUGCCCACGUCCUCUCCAGGAGGGGACACCGGGUUCACGAGCUGCCCACGCACUUUCCAGGAAGGGACCCCGGGUUCAGGUCUCCUGCCGGCCCACAUCGUGCCUUUGUGUAAAUCAGAAGAAAGAUGAGGAACAGGCCCUCCUCUCUCUCCAGGCAGGCUUUGGUGGAGGGGCUGGAUCUCCUGCCGCACCUUCCCUGGCAGGGCACCCUGUGCUUGAGCCCCAGAACUGCAGGCGGCCGGCAGAGAAGGGGUCCAUGAUGGCGCCUCGGUGCGCAGCCUUGGACCUGCCCCCAUGGACCUGGGUGAGGACUUCCCAGCCCUUCCCCGGCUCCAGCUGCUCUCCCUAAGGGCCGCCUCACCCCUUCCUCGGGCAGGGGGCAGUGGACGAGGGUUCCGUCCCUCCAGGGGAUGCUCCCAAACCCCUGCCAGGACUUGGCAGAUCCGGCCUCUCAUCUUGGCAGCUAGAUGGUGGGACGGGAUCAUCGUGGUGGCUUUAAUUUGCAUUUCUCUGAUGACUGAUGAUUUCGAGCAUCUCUUCAUAUGUUUGCUGGCUUUGGGGAUAGAGAUAUUUCUUCCUAAAGCAAAACUUGAUUAUGUCAUUUCUGCUUCAAGAUGCCAGUGAUGCCUGAGGUCUGCAGGGCAGUGCAGACGCUCACCGCCUGGCCGCUCAGGAGCCUGUGCUUGACCCCCAAAUCCGCCCCCCAACUCCCUGUUACCGGCUCACUCCUUCCAUGAGGGGCCUUCCCCAGGGACAGCCGAUGCUCUCCUGAUGGCUCCUGCCCUUGCAGAGUGCUGCCCCCGCCUGCCCACCUGGCCUGGACCCUCGCCUGAGCCCCCUCAGGGCUCUGCGCCACCUCAACCCAGGCGUUUGUUCCGCAGGAACCUCCCGGCUCUUCCCACUCGGGAAAGGAAGGCUCUGGGCAUGGAGGUCGGCCAGGCCCCAUCCCCGUACCCUGGCCCUUCUUCCUGCUUCCUGUUUGUCACUGCCCCGGGGCCUUUGCACCUGCAUUCCCUCUCUCUGUGAGUGUCCUGGGGCCCGUUACCCACGUCACCGUCCCAGGAUACCUUUUCUUUUCUUUCUCUCUCUCCAGCUUUAUUGAGGUAUAGUUGACAAUUCAGGACGGUGUGCACUCAAGGUAUGCAGCAUCACAACCUGACACACGUAGGCAUUGUGAAAUGAGUCCCACAAUUGGGCUAAUUAACACACCCAUCACCUUACAUGGUUACUUCUUUCUGUGGUGAGAACACUAAAUUUUAAAUAGAGGACACACAGCCUGGGCAACAUAGUGAGACCCUGUCUCUACAAAUAUAAAAAAAUUAUCUGGACGUGGUGGUGCACACCUGUGGUCCCAGCUACUUGGGAAGCUGAGGCUGGAGAAUCACUUGAGCCUGGGAGGCGGAGGUUGCGGUGCACUCCAGCCUGGGCGACAGAGGGAGGCCCUAUCUCAAAAUAAAUAAAUAAAGGACACAUUCUUAUCA